AGUGGACUUGGCGGCAGAGGCAGUGCGGAUCCGGCGUUCUCCACUGAUCUUUUCCAAGGCUGUACAGACAUGGCGGCGGCUUUUCGGAAGGCGGCUAAGUCCCGGCAGCGGGAACACAGAGAGCGAAGCCAGCCUGGCUUUCGAAAACAUCUGGGCCUGCUGGAGAAAAAGAAAGAUUACAAACUUCGUGCAGAUGACUACCGUAAAAAACAAGAAUACCUCAAAGCUCUUCGGAAGAAGGCUCUUGAAAAAAAUCCAGAUGAAUUCUACUACAAAAUGACUCGGGUUAAACUCCAGGAUGGAGUACAUAUUAUUAAGGAGACUAAGGAAGAAGUAACCCCAGAACAACUAAAGCUGAUGAGAACUCAGGACGUCAAAUAUAUAGAAAUGAAGAGGGUUGCAGAAGCUAAGAAAAUCGAAAGACUAAAAUCAGAGCUCCAUCUGCUGGAUUUCCAGGGGAAGCAACAGAACAAGCAUGUGUUCUUUUUUGACACCAAAAAGGAAGUUGAACAGUUUGAUGUCGCAACUCACCUGCAAACAGCCCCGGAGCUAGUCGACAGAGUCUUUAAUAGGCCCAGGAUAGAGACCUUGCAGAAAGAAAAAGUGAAAGGAGUUACCAAUCAGACUGGACUUAAGCGAAUAGCUAAAGAAAGGCAAAAGCAGUAUAACUGCCUGACACAGCGGAUUGAACGAGAGAAGAAAUUGUUCGUUAUUGCUCAGAAAAUUCAAACACGCAAAGAUCUUAUGGAUAAAACUCAGAAAGUGAAGGUGAAGAAAGAAACGGUGAACUCCCCAGCUAUUUAUAAAUUUCAGAGUCGUCGAAAACGUUGACGUGUUAUAGAUAAGCCUUGUCAUUCUGUAUCAAAAAUCUGUUGUCGUUUUCUAGUAACUUCAAAUUCCAUUACUCCAAAUGGCAUGGUUUUCCGGUUUGUAACCAUAACUAAAUUGUCAGUCUGACAUUUAAUGUCUUUCUAUGGACAACAUUAAAUCUCCCUCCCUUCUGUAAUUGUUUUUGGAUUGUGAAAUUAGUCUUAUUUUUAUAUACUUAAUUUUUUUUUUCUUUGAGAUAGGGUCUUUGUUGCCAGGCUGGAAGUGCAGUGUGUGAUUAUGGCUCACUGCAACUUUGAACUCCUGGGCUCAAGUGAUCUUCCUGCAUCAGCCUCUUGAGUAGCUGGGACCACAGACAUGUGCCACCAUGUCUGAGUAAUGUUUAAAUUUUCUGUAGAGACCAGGUUUUGCCAUGUUGGCCAGGCUGGUUUUGAACUCGUGGCCUCAAGCGAUCCUCCCACCUUGGCCUCCCAAAGGGCUGGGAUUACAGGGAUGAGCCACUAUGCCCAGCCCAUAAUUUUUUUUGUUAUGAAACAUAGGAUCUCAUUACAGCAGAUUUGGAAAGUAGAUUAAUUCAUUCCUAAUCCCAGUGCUUAUUCAAUAAUAACAAAUAUUUAUUGCAUGCUUAACUGUGCUAGGAGCUAGAGCUGUGGAGGUGGACAAUUACUGUGAGUAGUCUAGUUGAUUUCCUCCAUUUUGUAAAACGAGGCAUCACUUUUUGUCCAUGUUUUUGUGUUUUAUAGUUACAGUAAACAAUUUGAUGUCCUACUUUUUUUUUUUUUUUUUUUGAGACGGAGUCUCGCUCUGUCGCCCAGGCCGGACUGCGGACUGCAGUGGCGCAAUCUCGGCUCACUGCAAGCUCCGCUUCCCGGGUUCACGCCAUUCUCCUGCCUCAGCCUCCCGAGUAGCUGGGACUACAGGCGCCCGCCACCGCGCCUGGCUAAUUUUUUUUUGUAUUUUUUUAGUAGAGACGGGGUUUCACCUUGUUAGCCAGGAUGGUCUCGAUCUCCUGACCUCAUGAUCCACCCGCCUCGGCCUCCCAAAGUGCUGGGAUUACAGGCGUGAGCCACCGCGCCCGGCCGAUGUCCUACUUUUUAAUUAAAUCAUUAGCUCUUUCCCAGUUUGUUACAUCACAAAAGUUUUUUACAGUAAUAUAUGCUAGAGUAAACGUUAAAAUAAAUAUUAUUUUUAAUGA